UAUAUUCGGGACUCGGGGGCGGGUCGGCGCCAGAGACGAGAAGAGAGGAGGGGAGGCCUCCUCCGCCGCCGCCAUCUUGGACCGGGCCCGGUCAGCUUCCGCGGAGCCAUCGGCAGACGCCGCGGCCUCCCUUGAGCCCCGACCCCCGUCGUCAGAACAACCCCGGGCCCACUCCCCCAACCCCACUUCCGCUUCGCGCCGCUAUCGCGAUAGCGCCCGGGCCCGGGGCGCGAGAAAAAGGCGGCGGGCGCUCGCCUCCCCCGCCUGUCGCGAUACGCUCCUCAGCGGCGGCGCCAGCUCCUGUGGUGAGAGCGUCAGGCUCGACUGGGCCGGACCCCUUCCCUUCCUCCCCCCGGCGCCAUCGGCCGCCCUCCCCGCCGCCUCCCGCCCUGGCGACACCGCCGUCUGUCGCGACAUGGCCUCCCCUCGCCUGCCCCCUGCCGCCGCCUCUGCAGCGCGGGGCUCCCGGCGGGGGGCGGCUCCCUCCCUCUCGCCCUCCCGUUCCUGCGCCUCUUUCACGUUCCUCAGCGCCUCCCGGGGGUCCUUCCGCGACCCGGACCCCGGGCCCCGCCCGCCGCCGCCUCCCCGCGUGGCAUCGCGUCGGGCCCCCCGGUAGGGGUGUGAGGGUGCGAAGCCUCCCGGGCGCGAGGUGCCCGCCCCUCUCCGCGUCGGUAUUGGCUCCUGGCUGGAAGGAUGGAGGCGCCCCUGGUCCCAGGUGCCCGCCCUCUCGGGGCUCAGGUGCCUGCCCCCCUCGGCCUCGGUCCUUCGCGUUGUGGGGCAGCCUCCGCGCCGGGGCUUCUCCCUCGACGGUGGCGGGGAGGGGGGGUGGUGGUCGGGACGAGGACCCCAGCUGGGUGGGGGAGUCACCCUUCCCAGGACCGAGGCCGCCCUCCGCAUCCCUCCUCACUGCUCCCGGGAGCGCAGCCUCCCCUGGAUCUCAGGUUCCAGCUGCCCGUCUGUAUCGGAUGGGAGCCUCUUGGGAGAGGAGUGGAGGAGAAACUCCCCGUUAGUUGGAGCCUUUGCCGAAGUUUCCACCUCUGUAGUCUGCAGCUCUUCCCUCUCAUAGCGAGUAGCGCCCUGGGUGGCUCCAGCCUCGCCAUCCCGCUGCACUGGGCGCCUGCCUUUUUGGGGGAGUUUGGCUUUCCCCCACCUGGGGUACAGGACCGUCCUCAGUGUGGCCCACGUCUGGUCUCAGCUCUCACACUUCUUUGAUCCUGGCGUCUGCCCCUGGCUUUGCAGCCUUGAACUCCCCUGCAUCGUGACUCUCCGACCUUCUGGGUGUGGGCGUCUCCCAGUGAUAUCAGGACCACUGUGGUCUUGUUGCUGGGGGCUGCUGGGAUCCCCUGGCGCUCAGGUGCCUGGUGAAAGACACUAAGCCGCCACGCUGUCCAUGUUAGUGAGCUCCCACUGCGGGCAGCACCAGCCCCUCUUUCUGAGCAGUCCCUGCCUCUCAGUGCAGGGCGGCCACCCACCCCGGGGUGAGCUCUCCUGUCCUUUUGGUGAGGGGUUUUGAUGUCUCCCCUCCCUCCCUUCACCCCUGCCUGAGUAUGAGGCUUCUUCCAUCUUCACACCAGUCUCCUCCUUUAGGGUGUCAGCUCUCCAAGGACCAAGAAGCCCACUGCCCUUGAUAUUUGCAUCAGAUCCCACACUGUGGGUUUGUUGACUUCCCAUCUACCCUUACGCUGGGUGUCAGCAGUUGGAGAACAAGGGUUUCGCCUUCUGGCCCCGCUGCUGGUACCCCAUGAGAGUAGGAAGCUUCCUAGACCCGGGUUCCUGUACUGCGAGGUGGGGGCUCUUCCCUCUGGGGCUGUGCCUUCUCUCCAGGGUAAGGACCCUUUCUUGGUGUCACCUCCCCCAGGGAUAAGGUUCUUGCCAUCCUUGGUAUUGGUAUGGCUGCUUUUCUGGAUUUGAGGUGUCCACGCCUCUGCAUGUGUCCCCACCGUAAGGCUGAGGACCCCUCUCGGAUGCAGGUGCCCCCGGCUCAUGCUUCCAAAACCCCCUCUUGAUUUGUCACUGUAUGGGGUAAGGCAUAGUUUCCUGGCUGUGUGGAUGUAAGAUACCUGAGUCUCAAGCGGGAGACUCCACUGUAGACCCUGUCCCUGGGACCAGAGACUUCUCUGGUGUAGACUUUCCAAGGUGGGAGAUUCCAGCCCCCCACCCUUGGCAUGGGGCAUCUCAGUGGAGAUGACUACCUCUACCCCAGGCCCUAACGCAUCCUUCUUCUGGAGUCUCAGAGCCUCUGUGUGGCCACGUCAGCAGCCACCUGGGUUAAGGAUCACCCUUCAACAUCACUUCUCAGAGCUCCUUGCUGCAGAGGCGGAAGCUCUCCCAGAUCAAAGGUGCCUCAUGACAAAGACCACUCUGUGGGCACAUGACGGCCCCCAAGGUUAAGGACCACCCGGUGUUAGUUUCCCAGGGCUGACCUCCUGCCCCUCCCUCCUCGAGUCUUUGUGUGGUGGUAUCAUCUUCCCUGAGAUGAAGUCUGGGGGGCUCUUCUUUACUGGUUUUGGCUCUGAUUUUAGCGUGUUGGCUCCUGUGAGGCUGGUGUCCUGCUCACCUCCCCCCGCCCCGCCACCCGCCUUGUGGGUCCCUUCCCUGUGGGGAUGUGUGUUCCUCUUGGGUAAGUCUCCUCCUGGGCCGAGGUUCCCAGAUUCCUCAGUGCUCUUGGAGAGCCUUUGCUGCUGGAGCACAGGUUCUUCACGCCUGAGAGUGGACCUGCGAUCACCACCUUCCUUGGAGGAUCUUGGUGGAUGCCCCCCUGACUACAGCAAAUGGGGCUCUUUCUUCUCUGGCGGCGUCUCUGCUUCGAGACUCAGGCUCCAGCUUCCCUUCUCUCUGGUCCUUUGCUGGGGGGACCAGAGGUACAGAUACCCUCAUGAUAUAAGGAUUUUCUUAGCGGGGAAGGUGUUGUCUCUACUGUGGCUAAGGCUCCAGCCUCUCUAGGGGACAAGUACCCUGGGCCUCUGGCACUUGCCCCUUCUCUGUGGAGGAGCUGCCUCCUCACUGGGUCUCAGCUGUAGCCGACUUCGAUGUCACACUGUUCUGUCUGAAACAUCACCUCCCUGGGUUAGCGCUCUUGUUCCCCUCCUUCUGGCUUGUGACCCCUCCAGGACUUCCUUCUCUUGCUGCCACAGUGUGGUCUCCUCUCUGUGGGUAUUCUUCCUCUGCACUAGGAUACCAGUCCUUUCCGUGUGGAGACACAGGGAGGGCGUCACCUGCCUAAGGUGUUGAUUGCCUUGUUUAGGGGUGUAGACCAUGAGACCUCUUCUCUCUCUGGGCUGGAGCACCUGCCCAUGACCCUCUGUUGGGUUCUUGGGAUGGAAAGAGGGAGUGUAAACUCUCGUUUCACAUUCUUGUUCCCCCUAUGCAGUAAGAGGCUUUUCUGUGUUGGGGUGUUGGACUUUGGUGAGGAUCCCUGCACACCUGAGCUCUGGUGUCCAGGCCCUUGCCUUGUGUGAGCUCCCUGGGUCAAAGGGGCUUUCCCCUCCUCAGCCUGAAUCCCCACUGUGGCACCUUCUCCUGGGUCCUUUUGUUGGUUGCUUUGCCUUCUUAGAGAUUCCCCAGGUAGGGCGUGAUAGCUGACCUGGGCGGGGGCUGCUGCGGCUUUCUUUAGGUUGGGCCUUUUACUGAGGAGAUUUAAAUUCCCUCAAGUGUAAGGUAGCACCCCUACCUAUUAUCACCCAGAAUGGGUCCCUGCGGUGUUGGGAAAAUUCUCCCUGGGGGUAAGGUACCAGCCCUGUCCUUUAUGGGCUUCUUGUUCUAAAGCAUAUCCGUCCCAUAUGGUUGCUGCUAGUCACAUGUGGUGAUUAGUAACUAGUUAAAAAUGAAAAAUUCAGUUCCUCCAUUACACUUGCCACAUUUCAGAUGUUCAGUGGCCAACAGAUAUGCGCAAAUAGAGUGUUUCCAGCAUUGCAAAGUUCUGUUGGAUAGCACUGUUUGCCAGAUGUUCCCUUCUUUGUGGGUGAGGACUCUUUUGGUGUGACUUCCCUCUGUAUUGAGGCUCUUGUUCCUCAGUAUGGGGCUGUUUCUGUCUUUACAGUAAGUGACUACUCCAGGGUUCCCUGCCCUGCACACGUAGAGUGGGAGCGGCCCGUGGAUCCCAGGGAACUGUGCUUUUCAUUGUAGGCCCCCUCCCUGGAGGGGAAGAGGGCAAUCUCCGCUGGUAUCUCAGAAGUCUUCUUCUGAGGCAUAAGCCUCUCUUCCCAGGGCUCCCCUGGUCUCGCUGUCAGGCCCUAAGGUAUGUCUUCCCUUGGACUAAAGCUCCUUGGAACUCCCUUUUGACCUCAGUCUUCUCUGGGUUCCAGGUAACUUCCUUUAAAAUAAAGACGCUCCUCUCUUGAAGUUUUGGGUUCCUGCCCUGAUGGUCUAUGUCUCCCUGACUCUAAAUUACCAAUCCACUUGCUAUGGGAUUCCUCCAUGAGUGCAGAUCGGCUCCCUCACAGCUGCGGUACCUUUGCACCCUCUUAUCUUAGUAAGAUUUCUGUCUUCUCCCAGGUCUCUCUUGGGUACUGCCUUCUGCCCCCAAAUCUCUAAGCCUUCUUGGUAUUAGCUUCUUUGGGUUAGGAGUGUUAUUUCCUUUUGGUUUAAGGAUCCUGCUCUGGAAUAAAUGUCUUGGUGGUUUGAGUCCCUUCUACUUGGCAUUCAGCCCUGUCUGCAUGAGCGGGUUCAGCUCUUCACAGCUUUCGGCAUCUCUGCUCGCCGUCGUUUUCCCCCACCCCCAAUCUUUCUUCUCCUACCUACAGCUUACACACACACACACACACACACACACACACACACACACGCCCUUCUCUGUGAGCUGCCAGUUUCAUUUGUCUCCUGACUUGUCUGAGGGAUGACCUCUCCUAGCCACCUCUGCCCAGCCCCUCUGAGUAGGAAGUGUGAUUUCCAGGGCUAAUGCCUCCAUCCCAGUCAUCAGCUGUGUGCAGCAUGACUGUCCUGCUCUGAAAAACCUUUUUGAGUGUAUUCUGGGGAGAAGGUACUCCAUGCUCUAGGAAUUUUCCACUUCCUGAGUCAGAGGCACACAAAAAACGUCCGUCUCCAAGAGAGUAUGAAGAGAGUGCGUCUGUAGGGCAGGGAAGAUGGCGGACAAGCGCAAACUCCAAGGUGAGAUUGAUCGCUGCCUCAAGAAGGUGUCCGAGGGCGUGGAGCAGUUUGAAGAUAUUUGGCAGAAGCUCCACAAUGCAGCCAACGCGAACCAGAAAGAAAAGUAUGAGGCUGACCUAAAGAAGGAGAUUAAGAAGCUACAACGGCUGAGGGACCAAAUCAAGACAUGGGUAGCGUCCAACGAGAUCAAGGACAAGAGGCAGCUUAUAGACAACCGCAAGCUCAUUGAGACGCAAAUGGAACGGUUCAAAGUUGUGGAACGAGAGACCAAAACCAAAGCUUACAGCAAAGAGGGCCUGGGCCUGGCCCAGAAGGUAGAUCCUGCCCAGAAGGAGAAGGAAGAGGUUGGCCAGUGGCUCACGAAUACCAUCGACACGCUCAACAUGCAGGUGGACCAGUUUGAGAGUGAAGUGGAGUCACUGUCAGUGCAGACACGCAAGAAGAAGGGCGACAAGGAUCAGAAGCAGGACCGGAUUGAGGGCUUGAAGCGGCACAUCGAGAAGCACCGCUACCACGUGCGCAUGCUAGAGACCAUCCUGCGCAUGCUGGACAAUGACUCCAUCCUCGUUGACGCCAUCCGCAAGAUCAAGGACGACGUUGAGUACUAUGUUGACUCAUCCCAGGACCCCGACUUCGAGGAGAACGAGUUUCUCUACGAUGACCUGGACCUCGAGGACAUUCCACAGGCGCUGGUCGCCACCUCCCCUCCCAGCCACAGCCACAUGGAGGAUGAGAUCUUCAACCAGUCCAGCAGCACGCCCACCUCAACCACCUCCAGCUCUCCCAUCCCGCCCAGCCCAGCCAACUGUACCACGGAAAACUCUGAAGAUGAUAAGAAGAGGGGACGUUCCACAGACAGUGAAGUCAGCCAGUCUCCAGCCAAAAACGGCUCCAAGCCUGUCCACAGCAACCAGCACCCUCAGUCCCCAGCUGUGCCGCCCACCUACCCCUCCGGCCCCCCGCCUGCUGCCUCUGCCUUGAGCACCACUCCUGGCAACAAUGGGGUCCCCGCCCCCGCAGCACCCCCAAGUGCCCUGGGCCCCAAGGCCAGUCCAGCUCCCAGCCACAACUCGGGCACCCCUGCUCCCUAUGCCCAGGCUGUGGCCCCACCAGCUCCCAGUGGGCCCAGCACGACCCAGCCCCGGCCCCCCAGCGUCCAGCCUAGCGGAGGCGGAGGCGGCGGCAGCGGAGGUGGAGGGAGCAGCAGCAGUAGUAACAGCAGUGCCGGUGGAGGGGCUGGCAAGCAGAAUGGCGCCACCAGUUACAGCUCAGUUGUGGCAGACAGCCCGGCAGAGGUGGCUUUGAGCAGCAGUGGGGGCAACAAUGCCAGCAGCCAGGCCUUGGGCCCCCCUUCCGGCCCCCACAACCCACCUCCCAGCACCUCGAAGGAACCCAGUGCGGCAGCCCCAACGGGGGCUGGGGGCGUGGCCCCAGGCUCAGGGAACAACUCAGGGGGACCCAGCCUCCUGGUGCCACUGCCUGUGAAUCCUCCCAGCUCCCCAACGCCCAGCUUCAGUGAUGCCAAGGCAGCCGGUGCCCUGCUCAAUGGGCCUCCACAGUUCAGCACCGCCCCAGAAAUCAAGGCCCCUGAGCCUCUGAGCUCCUUGAAGUCCAUGGCGGAACGGGCAGCCAUCAGCUCUGGCAUUGAGGACCCUGUGCCAACGCUGCACCUGACCGAGCGAGACAUCAUCCUGAGCAGUACAUCAGCACCUCCGGCCUCAGCCCAGCCGCCCCUGCAGCUGUCAGAGGUGAACAUACCGCUGUCGCUGGGUGUCUGUCCACUGGGCCCUGUGCCCCUCACCAAGGAGCAGCUCUAUCAGCAGGCCAUGGAAGAGGCCGCCUGGCACCACAUGCCUCACCCCUCUGACUCUGAGCGUAUUCGGCAGUACCUCCCCCGGAACCCCUGUCCGACGCCCCCCUACCACCACCAGAUGCCACCCCCACACUCGGACACUGUGGAAUUCUACCAGCGCCUGUCGACCGAGACACUCUUCUUCAUCUUCUACUAUCUGGAGGGCACUAAGGCACAGUAUCUGGCAGCCAAGGCCCUAAAGAAGCAGUCAUGGCGAUUCCACACCAAGUACAUGAUGUGGUUCCAGAGGCACGAGGAGCCCAAGACCAUCACUGACGAGUUUGAGCAGGGCACCUACAUCUACUUUGACUACGAGAAGUGGGGCCAGCGGAAGAAGGAAGGCUUCACCUUUGAGUACCGCUACCUGGAGGACCGGGACCUCCAGUGACACCGGCCCCUCCCUCUACCCACCCCCUUCCCCCGCAUGCUGAUCCCCCUGCCCAGGUGAGGGCCCUGCCCUGGAAGACUGGAGGGAGGCCCCAAGCCACGGGGCAUCCCCCUCUCCCAGGAAGCAGGGAGGGGGCCGGGAGGUUUUCCUCUCAGCCCCACCCUGGGGGCCCGGGGGCGAGGGCUGCCCCCUCCUCCCCUCCCCAGUGAGGGACAUUUUUUGGUAAACCUAUUUUCAUUUUGGAAAAUAUUUAUGAAUAAAUAGUUUUAUAUGA